GGUGUCCGCAGACUGCCCAGAGGGCAGCCGCCUCACAGAUAUCUCCAUUUGCCAGGAGAUGCCCAGCCUGGAGGUGAUCACGCUCAGGUACCUCGCUCCUGCUGUCAUGCUCAGCCUGGGGCCUGGAAGCCGGGGCAGAGCCUCACGUCCCUCCAGUGGGACCCAGCACUGUGACAUAACCUGGAAACCUCCAACACAGACUGAGGGCGGCUUCCAGAAGGGGAGGGGCCGGGACAGCGAGAGCUGGGCCUACCCUGUGGCCCCCAUGUUCAGCCCUCCUUCCUCAGAGCCUCACCUGGGCCUCCUGAUGGCUCCUGUCCCCUGCCUGCCCUGCUGUACGCCUGCCCACCCUUGGCCUGUGUGCUCCGAUAAGCCAUUGCUGUGUUCACUGGGCCAGUCGGUGGUGGAGCCCUCCUAAGGAUUCACGGUGGCCCGCCCUGGCCGCCCCCACGGUGGCCACAUCUGCCCUGGGACCCCCAGAGUCCUGGCCUCUUCUGCCCCCCAGUGCCACCACUGCCUACCAGUUUCUCUGCACCCCAUGACCUGUGCCCGUCUUCUGGGGUCACUGCCCUCCCAGCAGACUAAGGGAAGCUUGAAUGAACAAAUGUUACUGGACUUUCAGGCAGUUGGGGUGUAUUUGGGGGCUCUGGGGAAGAGAAGAGCUCCCUUUAUCCCUGAAUUCCCUCCUGCCUACUGUGGGACCCACGGAGGGAGCAGACGCUCAUGGCUCACCACUGCCCACCAGACGCUGGAUGGGCGCCUUCUGUGGGUUUCCGCAUUUAAAAGCUCACAAGGGUUUAAACCCUGUGGGGAAGGCCCACCCCUCUGGCAGCUCAGAAGUCUCUAGGGCUUGCCCUCUGAGAGUGGGUAUUGCAGGCCCCUGGUCCCUGACUGUGACCUACCUUCUUGAUCUCACAGGCAGCCACGGGGUAGGCCAGCCCCUGCCCAUCCUCCGUAAUGCCCUCUGAGGUUGGCAUUGCCAUGUUGAUGCCCGUGCCCAGCCUGCUGCCCGCCAUGGGCUGAGGCCAGUCCAUCUGGUGUUCAGGCAUCCCCAGCGCGGGCACCAGCCUGUCCUGCCCGAGCCUUGCUGAAUGAAUGAAAUGGGCUUGGAGGCAUGCUCAUGGGUCAAAUCUCAGCCCUCCCAUCUAUUGGCUGGCUAACCUUGGGCGAGGCAUGGCCCUCUCUGUGCCUCAGUUUCCUUUCUGUAACAUGGAGGUAUUACAAGUGCCCACCCCACAGGGAGAUGAGGAGGAGAUGGAGCCCGAGUCCAGAGGUUGAGCAGGGGUGCGCGUGCCCGCCCAGAGGUUGAGCGGGGGGGGGGGGGGGGUGCGCGUGCCCGCCCAGAGGUUGAGGGGGGGUGCGCGUGCCUGCCGCGGGGCUCGUUUCACUAGUCAGGCGACACAGUGAGGCUGGGAUUUCAGGCCUGCCUCCGAAAGGCUUACCUGACAGGGAAACGUGGAGCUUGUGGUUCCCACGGUGGCAGGAAGCUUGGGGCGGGGCUGUGGAUCCAGCCCUAUCCCUGCCGCUCACUGAGUCACCCAGGGGCCACAGGGCCUCCGAGCAUCAGGCCGCUCGUGUGUGGGGCCAUUUCUGUCACAUCUCGGGAGGGACAGGACCCCAGGGGUGUUGACCGAGCUCAGGUGCGUGGUGCCUGCACGCCUGACUGCACUGGAGCGGAGCAGGAAGCCUCGAGGCCGCGGACGCGGUCGGUACAUCACGCUGCUGCCUGUGCCUGAGGCAGACCCCAUCCUGGAAAGAGUCCCACAGCCGGAGUUUUGCUCUUGGUAAAAUGGGGCGGCCUCAUAGCUAGGAGCUGCAUGAGACCUGGGAAACCCCGAGUGAAGGGAUGGCAUGGGGAGGGGGGCUCAGGACGGCAGGCUGCCCAUGGGGGCCUGGUGACCGCCCUUCUGAGGCGCCUGCCGGACGCGAGUGCAGCCCUCCAGGCAGGGGGCCCUGGCUCCGCGCCUUUGAGGGCCUGCGGGAGCGGCUCCGCGUGUUCGCUUGUGGAGGGGACGGACCCCACGCUGCAGGGUAAAGCCUGCAGGUCCCCGCUCCAGGCCUGCUGUUUCUCUUCUCUGACGCGUCCACGUUCUGUAGAAUGGAAAUGAGGCCCAUCCCCAGUGUUGCCGCCCUCAAGUGGGGGUUUGGAAGGUCCGUGCUCACUCCCAUGUCACGUGGAGCUGGCUCCUAGUUUUUGCCAUGAGUUUUUCUGGCCGCUCCCUGCUUUGGGGCAACAUGAUAUGUCCCCUGAGAGGCCUUAAUUUUCCUCACCUGUGAAGGAGGGCCACAUCCCCCACCUCCCGCACUCUAGCGCCCUGAGGAGCUGAUGUGGAGCGUCGGGCCAAGGGGCUGUUGCUGGUGGGGUCCACCCCAGUCCGCCUUUGAGUUCAGGGCCUGGCCUUCCUACAGCUCUCUCCUCGGCCCAGGUCCUGCUGCACGUGACUUGUGACAUCCGAUUUAGGCUUCUCAGGAGAGGGCAGGGACACAGGUCCCAUGAGUGCCUUUUACUGGGGGUGGGGAUUGAGAGGUGGCCCUGGGGGCCCUGGCCACGUCCCUCGCUGACUGUGCUGGUCUCCGUGCAGUGUCAACAGCAUCUCCACCCUGGAGCCUGUGAGCCGGUGCCAGCGCCUGAGUGAGCUGUACCUGCGGAGGAACCGCAUCCCCAGCCUGGCUGAGCUCUUCUACCUGAAGGGGCUGCCGCGUCUGCGGGUGCUGUGGCUGGCCGAGAACCCGUGCUGCGGCACCAGCCCCCACCGCUACCGCAUGACCGUGCUGCGCACCCUGCCGCGCCUACAGAAGCUGGACAACCAGGCUGUGACGGAGGAGGAGCUGUCCCGUGCACUGAGUGAGGGAGAGGAGAUCACUGCGGCCCCAGAGAGAGAGGGCACAGGCCACGGCGGCCCCAAGCUAUGCUGCACACUGAGCUCCCUCAGCUCCGCUGCUGAGACUGGCCGGGACCCGCUGGACAGCGAGGAGGAGGCAACCAGCGGCGCCCAGGAUGAACGUGGCCUGAAGCCGCCUUCCCGGGGCCAGUUUCCUUCCCUCUCAGCCAGGGAUGCCUCGAGCAGCCACAGGGGCAGGGUGAGUGGCGGGCCGCUAGGGGCCGCGGCUGCCUCUGCCCACUGCACCCACUGCACAGAAACCGUGGGGAGGGAGCAUGGAGCCUCACAGGGCCCCGUGGGGAGGGAGCAUGGAGCCUCACAGGGCCUUGAAGAGCUGUGCCCCAGGGGGAGCUGCGUGUGCGGGUCUGUGAAUGCGCACACACGUGUAACACGUGCCCCGCACGGAGCCGUCCUGGCCCCUCAGCCUCUCCUGCUGUCCUGGUCUGUGGAAUGUGGGCCCGGGCCCUGCUGGGCUGAGGGCAACAGGAGUCACGUGGAAGAGGUGCCACACACGCGUCCACAGGCGGGGCUCCUCUGCUCAGAUUCUCCGAGUGUGCCGAACGUCCUGACUGCCAUCCUGCUGCUGCUGCGGGAGCUGGAUGCAGAGGGGCUGGAGGCCGUGCAGCAGACUGUGGGCAGCCGGCUGCAGGCCCUGCGUGGGGAAGAGGUGCAGGAGCACGCCGAGUGACCGCAGGACCUGAACGCCGCUCCAGCCUCCACGGGGACCCCAGCGUCUUCCCCAGCCCCCGGGAGCUGGAGGGUGGCUGCCAUGGCCGCAGCCCCGGCCCCACACAAAAGCCUCCCCGGUUUGCCACAUCGGCCGAGGGCAGGAGUGGGUGUUAGGUACUGGCUAACCGGGGCGGUGGAGAUGCCUGUCUACACCAGUCCUGUCCCCAGGACUCCCCUUCUGUGGUCUGGAGGUUCUAGGCUGGCCUGGGCUCUUAAAGGGAGGAUUUUGCAGGCUGUCCUCCCUAAUAAAAGAUUUUCCCAAGGUUGAUCUGGAGGUGACGUUUCCCAAGGCAUGGUUGUGACAGUCUUCCUGAAAGCAAGGGCCGUUUCUCCACAGAAUGAGGAGGUCUUCACGGAUGGCUUUGCCGAUUCCAGCCCUUGGUCCUUGGAUAGAUUUCUGUUGGGCAAGGGAGACUUCGAGAAUGCUGGCACCCAUAGCGACAUCUGCCCUGAGCUGCUCAGCAGGCAGGCAGCAGCCUCCCGCACCCAUGGGAGAGAGUUUUGUUUUCUUGGCCGGGCUGGGCAGGUGCGCCUUCCUUUCUCUCUCCUGUGAAGAACUGCAGGAGGGCCCUCAGCUGUGAGGUUGUGGAUGAACAGGCCUGUUCGCCCUGGGGUCCGGGCCUGGCACAGGAAGCAGCUAGACUAGGGGAGUCCUUGGAGCAUCUGAGAGGGGUUUUCUUUCCUCUGGGAAGAGUCGCAAGUCUUAUGAGGAUGCCACAAUCUGGGCAGUGACCCGUGGCCCUGGGGACCUUCCUAGUGCCCCCCAAAACCAAGGAAGCAUUCACGUGAGAUGGGGAGUCAGCCUUCCAGCUGGUGUGUAGGAAAGCCAGGUCCCUGGGCCCUUGUCCCAUGUGGGGUUGAGAUCCAGAUCUCCAUGAGAUAUUCCCAUCCUCCGCCGAGCGGUGAUGCGUGACCGUGUGUGCAGGCCGCUGUUCUCCCAAGCUCGGGGCCAUGCCGUGCCACCGUCACCAGAGCCAGCUGCAGCACUGGGGCAGCCACUGUCGCCGGACUUGGGGAAGCCCAGGGUGAAGACAGUCACUCAUCCGUGCAAGCUCUCCAGAAGGGAUGCAAGCUCUCCAGAAGGGGUGUGAUCUCUGAGCAGUGGGGAGUGGAGUCACCACUCGGGACAUAGAGGGUGGACAGUUCAGGCCUGUGUCUGCCUCCUUGGGACUGUGGAGUGGGUGCCCUCAGUAAAGCGCUUUGUUGGAAUGGU